GCAGCUCCGGUGCAAGCGAGGACACGACACAUGCAGUGGCUUCUGGACUGCGCGAUGACUGGACGCAAGUAACUUCUAGGUCUGCAGACAAGAGGAAGAGAAGAUGAAGGAAGACUGUCUGCCGAGUUCUCACGUGCCCAUCAGUGACAGCAAGUCCAUUCAGAAGUCGGAGCUCUUAGGCCUGCUGAAAACCUACAACUGCUACCAUGAGGGCAAGAGCUUCCAGCUGAGACACCGUGAGGAAGAAGGGACUCUGAUCAUCGAGGGGCUCCUCAACAUUGCCUGGGGGCUGAGGCGGCCCAUCCGGCUGCAGAUGCAGGAUGACCGGGAGCAGGUGCACCUCCCCUCCACCUCAUGGAUGCCCAGACGGCCUAGCUGCCCUCUAAAGGAGCCAUCGCCCCAGAACGGGAACAUCACAGCCCAGGGGCCAAGCAUUCAGCCAGUGCACAAGGCUGAGAGUUCCACAGACAGCUCGGGGCCCCUGGAGGAGGCAGAGGAGGCCCCCCAGCUGAUGCGGACCAAGAGCGACGCCAGUUGCAUGAGCCAGAGGAGGCCCAAGUGCCGCGCCCCCGGUGAGGCCCAGCGCAUCCGGCGACACCGGUUCUCUAUCAACGGCCACUUCUACAAUCAUAAGACCUCCGUGUUUACUCCAGCCUAUGGAUCCGUGACCAAUGUGAGGGUCAACAGCACCAUGACAACCCUGCAGGUGCUCACCCUGCUGCUGAACAAAUUUAGGGUGGAAGAUGGCCCCAGUGAGUUCGCACUCUACAUCGUUCACGAGUCUGGGGAGCGGACAAAAUUAAAAGACUGCGAGUACCCGCUGAUUUCCAGAAUCCUGCAUGGGCCAUGUGAGAAGAUCGCCAGGAUCUUCCUGAUGGAAGCUGACUUGGGCGUGGAAGUCCCCCAUGAAGUCGCUCAGUACAUUAAGUUUGAAAUGCCGGUGCUGGACAGUUUUGUUGAAAAAUUAAAAGAAGAGGAAGAAAGAGAAAUAAUCAAACUGACCAUGAAGUUCCAAGCCCUGCGUCUGACGAUGCUGCAGCGCCUGGAGCAGCUGGUGGAGGCCAAGUAACUGGCCAACACCUGCCUCUUCCAAAGUCCCCAGCAGUGGCAGGUGUACACUGAGCCCUGGUUGCUGGCCCCGGCCGGUCACAUUGACUGAUGGCCACCGCCUGACGAAUCGAGUGCCUGUGUGUCUACCUCUCUGAAGCCUGAGCACCAUGAUUCCCACAGCCAGCUCUUGGCUCCAAGAUGAGCACCCACAGGAAGCCGACCCAGGCCUGAGGGGCCAGGAACUUGCUGGGUCAGAUCUGUGUGGCCAGCCCUGUCCACACCAUGCCUCUCCUGCACUGGAGAGCAGUGCUGGCCCAGCCCCUGCGGCUUAGGCUUCAUCUGCUUGCACAUUGCCUGUCCCAGAGCCCCUGUGGGUCCACAAGCCCCUGUCCUCUUCCUUCAUAUGAGAUUCUUGUCUGCCCUCAUAUCACGCUGCCCCACAGGAAUGCUGCUGGGAAAAGCAGGGCCUGCCAGCAGGUAUGAGAUCUAGCCUGCUUUCAGCCAUCACCUUGCCACAGUGUCCCCGGCUUCUAAGCCUCCAAUAUCACCCUGUGAGCCUCGCACAGCUCAGCCCCAACACAGAGGUGAGACCAGGAAUAAGGCCACAAGUAUCUCACUUUCUCUGCAGAAAUCAAUCUUUACUUCAUCAGAGAGACCUAAAGCGAUUCUUACAAGGAGCUUGCUGCAAGAAACACGGUCAUUCAAUCACAUUGAGGAGGGUCCACAUGGCAUUGAGAGGGUGCUGCCCGCUCAAUGCCCAGCAGCAGCUCUGGAAGGCAGUGCUCAGCCCCAUCACCACUGUCCCGUGGAUGCCUGUGUACCUCUUGCCUUUUCUGGGCUUGCGUUUCUCUCCUCUAGUGGGUGGGGAUGACUUUCAAUGACUUUCAAUACUUCCCCUGAAGGAAGAAUGAUAAGGAGAAAUGUCUGUUUUGAGGAAAGGGCUUUGAAUUCCCCAGAUACUGAACAAUUUGUGUUUGUGACUGAUGGAGAAUUUCAGGAAUGAAUGAGAAAGCCUUUGCGAAACUAUGCAACAGUUUACAUCAGUCAUGUGAAGUAUUUGUCUAAAACAGAGCAAACUGAAGACCAAAUUAUUCUCCUGUUGAGGUCCGUGGAUGGCAGAUUUAAAGGGAAGAACCACAAAGGCUUGCAAAGAUAGGAGAGGCUCCAUCUCUAAUGCAUGUAGAAGCUCCUUACGGGUGCCCAUCAAGAGCAUAGCUUGGAAGCCACCAUGCUGUGCGGAACUGCGUCAGGGCAAAUGUCACAGCAGGAUUUCCCCAACCCAGCUCCAUCAUCACAGACACAGAGAGCUGCAGGGGAGGCCUGCCCACUGUUUUGUCGACUCUGCCCUCCUCUGGCAGCAUAGAUCCUUAGGUGCUCAAUAAAGGUGUGCUGUAUUGAACUGAAGAAGUGAGAACCAAGCUUUUUUUUUUUUUUUUGCUUUCUGUGCAUCCACCCUGACCCCCGGCUCUAACUUCUGAAACUCUUAUCCUAAAGGAUGUGUGGCCAUGUUUGGCAGAAGAGCCACAACUCGCUGCUCUAGGAGCCGACAUGACUCCUUCAUUUCUGUGCAUGCCCUGGGGACUAGGGUGGAGCCUGAGGAGAGGCUGCCAUGGAACACGCAGGCGUCACUGGUGGGAGCCUAGAGGUGACCUGGAUGAUGAGCAAUAGAGUCACCCCGAGUCACAGAAUCUUAGCAUCAGGAGGGCCCCAAGAAUCUUCCAGGCCAGGGGCUCAGGUGGGAUGGAAGCAGGGCCUAGGAGAGGGUACAAAACAAAUCAAACAGGAGCUCCCAGGUAAUUGUACUCCCAAGCUAUUAUUUACAAUCUCAGGUGGAGGACAGCUCCUGUCCCAUUGUUCAGCUGUAACUGAGUGACUGCCUUGUGCCAGGCCUGUGCUCAGCCCUGGAGGCACAAAGAUGGAGCCAGUCUGUCCUGUGUCUAGGGGUCUUCUCAUCAGGAGAAGAAGGCCAGACACUGGAAGGGUCAAGAGAUCAGCUGAGCAACGAACCGGCAAAGCUCCUGGGAGUGAGGUGGAGGCCAAGGCAGAGUUGGCUAAGAAGUGCAUGUGGCGUCACAGGCCAAGAUGCACCUGCCAGCUAGGAGCAGGCCAGGUCCUGGCACACAGGAAGCCAGUGGAGCAGGAGACCCUCCCUAAGUACCAGCCUGUUUGGUUGGUUGGUUUGCUUUUGAAAGUUAUUACAAUAUUAUUUAAGGCCUUUUCGGAUAAGUUCACUUUUAAAGUAGGUGUUAUCAAUCUAAUUUCUGAACGUUAUGGGUCAGAAAAAUCACUAGCAAGUGGCUCAGAAAAAGGGAAAAGGUACACUUCUGCAAUCAGCUGAGGAGUUCACACCUUUUUUUCUAAAUCAACAUCAUAUUUGCUGUUCAGAGGCAAUCUGAAAAGCUGCAAAUUCAGCUCACCUCAACCCCAUAAUUUCAAACGUUAGAGGCUGGUCUCUGUGGUUUCCUACUGGUUCCUGUGGGGAGCUCCCGCUUUCUUUCUACAUAGAGCUUAGGGUAUUUCUCAUAUGCCCCAUUGGCUACCUAGUGUCUCAGGUAAUAAACGUAUCCGAAGAUAAAGCAAA